GAGGUGAGUGCCGGGCGAAUGGCUGCUGUCCAGGGGCGGGGGGGUGGGAAUUAGAAAGCACAGACAGGGUUGGGCUGAGGAAGUUAGAAGUGGUUAGUGGGGGUUGGCGGGGUAGGGAGAAAGGCUAGGGGUUGAGGGGGUGUGAAGGAGAUCUUUUUAGGCUGGCCCCUCAUAGCGCCCGCGAUCCUGUUUCUGCCAUAUGGCAUCCGUUCGAGGGUUCUCUCGCGUUUGUGCGCUCAAGGCAGAGGGAGGGUAUAACGGGGAGGCGAUUCGGCCGAGGACCUUGUACUUGACCCCUGAAGGGAUGGGCACCGCGGAGCCCAGAGGCCAGAGCCAGCUGCCAGGGCAGGGAUGGAGGUGGGGGACCAGGAGGAGCUUCGGGACCUCUUCAACUCCCCUUUACUCCGUCUUCCCCCUAAGGAGGAACAAGAGCGGGAUGUGUUGGGGGUGGGGAAUGUCUUGGGGCUGUACAAGCUCGCUGAGACUUUUCGGGGCCCGCCGUUUCCGCGUGCCCGCGCGACUCUCGACAAUGGACAGUGUACAGUGGUGGCAGGGUUUCACGGGUCCCCGCGCCGAUUUGGGAAUGGUACGGGGUGCCCUUGCAUUAGAGAAGCCUGUGCGGGCCCCCGGGAUUAGAGAAGAGGUGAGCGCCUGCGGGCGGGGAGAGAAGGACGCGCUGCUGGCAAAAAGAAGGGCGCCUUCCAUGGACUGGAGGAGCGGCGAGGGAGCCUGGUAUGUGUGUUUUGGAUUUGAAGGAGGCAAACCGCAUCGGAGAGUGCAAGUAGAUGCAGUGCGUCGGGGCAAAAGGACAAUCUGAGGAGUGAGAGUAACACAUGCGCACUGUGGAUUCCUUUGUGAAUACAUAAAAGGAAAAGUUAAAACUCUUAUAAUUCACACUAUCCAGAGAAAAACAAUACUAUUUUGCUAUGAAGUCUUACACUCCAUAUUUCAUUCUCCUGUGGAGUGCUGUUGGGAUAGCGAAGGCUGCCAAAAUCAUCAUCGUGCCGCCAAUUAUGUUUGAAAGCCAUAUGUACAUUUUCAAGACGCUAGCCUCAGCCUUGCACGAGAGAGGCCACCAUACAGUGUUCCUCCUCUCUGAAGGCAGAGACAUCGCCCCAUCUAAUCAUUACAGCCUCCAGCGCUACCCAGGGAUCUUUAACAGUACCACCUCAGAUGCUUUCCUACAGUCCAAGAUGCGGAAUAUUUUCUCUGGGAGAUUGACAGCAAUCGAACUGUUUGACAUACUGGAUCACUAUACUAAGAACUGUGACCUGAUGGUUGGCAACCAUGCCCUGAUCCAGGGUCUGAAGAAAGAAAAAUUUGACCUGCUGCUGGUGGACCCUAAUGAUAUGUGUGGAUUUGUGAUAGCUCAUCUUUUAGGGGUUAAAUAUGCUGUAUUUUCAACUGGCCUUUGGUAUCCUGCUGAAGUGGGUGCUCCUGCUCCAUUAGCAUACGUCCCAGAGUUUAACUCACUCCUCACAGACCGCAUGAACUUGCUGCAAAGGAUGAAAAAUACCGGUGUUUACCUCAUUUCCAGAUUAGGGGUCAGCUUUCUGGUUCUUCCCAAAUAUGAAAGGAUAAUGCAGAAGUACAACCUGCUGCCAGAGAAGUCCAUGUAUGAUUUGGUUCAUGGGUCCAGCCUGUGGAUGCUGUGUACUGACGUAGCACUGGAAUUCCCAAGACCCACUCUGCCUAAUGUUGUUUAUGUAGGAGGAAUCCUAACCAAACCAGCCAGCCCACUACCAGAAGAUCUCCAAAGAUGGGUAAAUGGUGCUAAUGAACAUGGCUUUGUCUUGGUGUCUUUUGGAGCUGGUGUCAAGUAUCUGUCAGAAGACAUUGCUAACAAACUGGCAGGAGCUCUGGGGAGAUUGCCUCAAAAAGUGAUUUGGAGGUUUUCUGGACCCAAACCAAAGAAUCUAGGAAACAACACUAAACUCAUAGAAUGGUUACCACAAAAUGACCUGCUUGGGCAUUCAAAGAUUAAAGCCUUCCUGAGCCAUGGUGGUUUGAACAGUAUUUUUGAAACUAUAUAUCAUGGUGUGCCUGUAGUGGGAAUUCCACUCUUUGGAGACCAUUAUGAUACUAUGACCAGAGUACAGGCAAAAGGCAUGGGGAUAUUGCUAGAAUGGAAGACAGUUACUGAAAAAGAGCUCUAUGAAGCACUAGUGAAGGUUAUCAAUAAUCCCAGCUACCGUCAGAGGGCUCAGAAGCUUUCGGAAAUUCACAAGGAUCAACCUGGUCACCCUGUCAAUCGAACUAUCUAUUGGAUAGAUUAUAUUAUUCGUCACAAUGGAGCCCAUCACCUACGUGCCGCUGUCCAUCAGAUCUCCUUUUGUCAGUAUUUUUUACUGGAUAUUGCCUUUGUGCUUUUGCUUGGUGCUGCCUUGUUAUACUUUCUCUUGUCUUGGGUGACAAAAUUUAUCUACAGAAAAAUCAAAAGUCUGUGGUCUAGAAAUAAGCAUAGCACAGUUAAUGGACAUUACCACAAUGGAAUCCUCAAUGGCAAGUACAAAAGAAAUGGCCAUAUUAAACAUGAAAAGAAAGUGAAAUGAGCCAACAGCCCAGGUGAUAGAAAUAAAUUGGUUCACUCAUUGAAUUUUUAUUGCUAUUAUUUAGUCUAACAGCUACUAAAAGUAAAACAUCAGUAAACAAUUCUAACAUGCCCUUAUGAGAUCUACUAAUGAAAUUCUGUGGAAUUAAGAUGGCUGUAAAAAGCACAAACCUAAAAUGCAGAAAUGUAUUUUAUUCAAAUACUGAUGUAGAGAGUUUUGGCACUGAACCUUUUAGAAGCCUUAAUUAUUUAAAUCAAUUCAGUGACUGUGUCAGACCUUAGUUUUAAAUCUUGAUAUGUGCGUGUCCCGGAUCAGGAAUGGUUUCAUUUUUCUUAAUAAUGUGUGUGUGUGUAUGUGUGUGUGUGUGUGUGUGUGUUUGUGUGUGUGUGUGUGUGUCCUAAUUAAGAGAAUUUUUACUGGCUGCUUGUUACAUUUGUUGAGGGUACAACACACUCAAGAAUAAAGUAAAAGGAUAGUCAGGAUCCAGAUGUUUCUUUUCUAGCAUUUAAUGUGUGUGAACUCAGAACACUACCAUGAAAGAACACUUCCCCCCAAAACUGGAUGCAGAGGAAGAAAAAAAAAAAAGAAAUGGCACAGUUUUUUGUAUUUUUUUUUUUAGUUAUUUUUUGUUGUUGUUGUUUGUAUUGUUUUUCUUUUCUGAUAGAGUAUGGCCACUUCUGGGGGAAAAACAUGUAAUUAAGUAAAUGUAUACAUUGGUUUUCACGUUUUACUUUUGUUUUCCCACUACCAAUAAUUUUCCUCUGGAAGAAUUUUAUAGUUUUUUCUAUUUCAUUUUAAUGAGUAACAAUAUGUUAAAUGCAUAAUUAAGACAAAGCAAUGAAAUUCUGACUUUAUUCAAAGUACUGAAGAUUAUUGCUUCUAGGGCAUUUUUAAACAGCACCAUUGUAUUGUUGAAUGUUUAUGUAACUGAUGGCUUUUCUAUAAUGUAAUUUUUGAAUGUUCAGGUGUUACAUUUCCAAAGUUUAACUUUUAAAAAACCAUCUUCUGAUCCCUUUUAUUGUCUGGGCCAUACAAUCUAUAUUACAUAGGUGCCAACAUUUAAUUCUUUUAAAUGGAACAUUUGCAGUUUUCCAUAUUGGUACCUGCUUUUUCUGGAGAGGUUUGAGAUCUUGUUAACAAAUCAGACUUUACACUAUAUACAGAUGUGACAGAUAAAUUGAACCACUUGUUUGUGAAAAUGAGUUCCUGUCAUCUUCCUCAUUCACUCAGCCCUCACCCCAGCAGCCUUUUCCGGUCAUUGUAGCUGACAUGGAGCAGUGACAGUAUUCAUUUGAGAACAGGGAUGCAAGUCACAGACAUCAUAAAAUCAGGGUCUCCCUGCUGAAGCAUUCACUAGUUGGCAACUAUGAAUUUAUUCCAUGUCAUUCUGUUUACUUAGCACUUGCACUACCCUUGUUGGUUGAGUGUAUGCUUUAUUUGUUUCUAGUUUGAAAUCCCACAUCUGAUAGCUGAGAGUAGGCAAAUACAACAUUUACCUAAUGUCAUUCACUAACAUGGAAGAGUUGUGAAAAUUCUAGAGUGCUGUAAAUCCUUGGCAUACACUAUGACAAACAACUUCAUUACUCUCCCACCAGGAGCUGCUCUCCUGCACUUAGAAAUAAUGUCACAAGUAGUUUUCUAAUGUACAAUGCAGACAAAUGUACUGCUCUCUGAAUACUUGAAGAAAUGGUAUUAUACAUACAUAGAAACUUAUUAGUUAUACCUUUUCACAAUCUUAUUACGAUGUUGCCGUUAAAAGGGAAAAAAGACACAGGCAAUGAAUGGUGGGAUAGUAAGAGGACUUAGAGUGUAUGAAUGAGUUGAUUUUACUUUUUUGGAAUUUGAUUAAGUUGACAGUAGGCACUGAUUGGAUGAUUAAACAUAAGUUAAUCUCCACUGUGAUAAAAACUUAAAUAAUAAACAUGAUUUAAAAUAGA